CUGGCGACUGCACAAGCAGGGAUGGCGUCGCUUCAGCGUUCUCGGGUGCUACGCUGCUGCAGCUGCCGCCUCUUCCAGGCGCACCAGGUAAAAAAGAGUGUCAAGUGGACAUGCAAAGCUUGUGGAGAGAAGCAGUCCUUUUUGCAGGCUUAUGGUGAAGGCUCUGGUGCUGAUUGUAGACGCCAUGUCCAAAAGUUAAAUCUACUACAGGGACAAGUUUCAGAGCUGCCACUCAGGUCUCUAGAAGAAACUGUCAGUGCCAGUGAAGAAGAAAACGUGGGACACCAGCAGGCUGGGAAUGUGAAGCAGCAGGAAAAAUCGCAGCCCUCAGAGAGUCGCUGGCUGAAGUAUCUAGAAAAGGACUCCCAAGAACUGGAGCUGGAAGGAACAGGAGUGUGUUUCAGCAAACAGCCUUCAUCCAAAAUGGAGGAGCCAGGCCCCCGCUUCAGUCAAGACCUGCCUAGAAAAAGGAAGUGGAGCAGGAGCACCGUCCAGCCUCCGUGCAGCCGUGGCGUGCAGGACUCGGGUGGCUCUGAGGUCGCCUGGGGACCCCAGAAGGGACAGGCUGGCCUGACAUGGAAGGUGAAACAAGGCAGCAGCCCCUGCCUCCAGGAGAACUCUGCAGACUGCAGUGCCGGGGAGCUGAGGGGUCCUGGGAAGGAGCUAUGGAGUCCCAUCCAGCAGGUUACAGCCACAUCCUCUAAAUGGGCGCAAUUUGUCCUGCCACCUAGAAAAAGUUCACAUGUGGACAGUGAGCAGCCAAGGUCUCUUCAGAGGGACCCCAGGCCAGCUGGUCCAGCACAGGCUAAGCAAGGGACCCCCAGAGCACAGGCCUCAAGAGAAGGCCUCAGCAGGCCCACUGCCGCUGUCCAGCUUCCUCGGGCCACACACCCCGUCACAUCUGGGUCUGAGAGGCCUUGCGGGAAGACCUCAUGGGACGCAAGGACUCCCUGGGCAGAGGGUGGGCCCCUGGUCCUGGAGGCACAGAAUCCUCGACCCACACGACUAUGUGACCUCUUUAUAACUGGGGAAGACUUCGAUGAUGAUGUGUGAUCUGGGACUGGCAGGUUAUUAAUCGAGAUACACUUGUUAGGAGGGACAGGGUUCCCCUAAGGCACUUUUAAAGAUACUCUGUAAGAACCAUUAACAAUAAACUUACUGUCAAUCA